CUUCCUCCUGCCCGUAGUAGCCAUGGCGGCCAUGAGUUUGUUGCGGCGGGUUUCGGUUACUGCGGUGGCAGCUCUGUCUGGCCGGCCCCUUGGCACUCGCCUCGGAUUUGGGGGCUUCCUCACUCGUGGCUUUCCGAAGGCUGCUGCUCCUGUUCGACACAGUGGAGACCAUGGGAAAAGACUAUUUGUCAUCAGACCUUCUAGAUUCUAUGACAGGCGUUUUUUGAAGUUAUUGAGAUUCUACAUUGCAUUGACUGGGAUUCCAGUAGCAAUUUUCAUAACUCUGGUGAAUGUAUUCAUUGGUCAAGCUGAACUAGCAGAAAUUCCAGAAGGCUAUGUCCCAGAACACUGGGAAUAUUAUAAGCAUCCCAUAUCAAGAUGGAUUGCCCGUAAUUUCUAUGAUAGUCCUGAAAAGAUAUAUGAAAGAACAAUGGCCGUCCUUCAGAUUGAAGCUGAAAAGGCUGAAUUACGGGUAAAGGAGCUGGAAGUGCGAAAAUUGAUGCAUGUGAGAGGAGAUGGACCCUGGUAUUACUAUGAGACAAUUGACAAGGAACUUAUUGAUCAUUCUCCGAAAGCAACUCCUGACAAUUAAGCAUUUUUUUCUCCAAAUACAAAGUAUAUUCUCUUUAUUGGAAAAUAAAUUAAUAAAUAUAUUCUGUAUUUUUGCUCUCCGUGAAAAACAAAAGAGCCUCUGACAUUACUGUCUCUCAGUGUUGGUUCAGAUUGAGGCUUUUGUUUGAGGAGUUUGGCUUCCAGUCCCCAAAGAAGGUUUAAAAUGUACUAAUAAAAACUGGAGAAAUAGGAAUUUGUGAACUCCUAAAAUUGUAGCAACUUUGAAAGGUUAGUGUUUUAUUUACCUGACAAAUGGAAGUUAUAGAAGUCUAAUAAUGUUAAGCACCAGUAAUUAUAGUAUUUUGUACAAAUGCCUGUACUGUAGAUGUCUGUAUUAUUGAGGGGCAACUCAGGAUUUUAAGUUCCAUAAAGUAUUGAACCAACUCUAAAAUGUUAACUCCUUAAUAAACAGAUUCUCAGUAAACAAAUUUUAAAGUUUAUAAUGCUUUCAUGGUUUUUUUUUUUGCCAUGUAUUGUUCUUUUUUAAACUACACACAGACACACAGACACGUACACACACACACACACACACACACACACACACGCUCUUUUCCUAGAUGCAAUCUCUGGGAUCCCUUAGAGUCCUUUUUUGGGGAAGUAGUUGCACUAGGUAAUGUGAUUCCUGCAGAGAUUAUAAAAUGUGAGUAAAAGCUAAAAAUGACUCAUUUAUUAAGCAUUUAUUGUCUGCUAGACACUAUAUUAAAUAACUGCAUUUUUUAACAUUAUUUUCUUUUCUUUUUUUUUUUUUUUUUUUUUGACGAAAUCUUGCACUGUCACCCAGGCUAGAGUGCAGUGCCGUGAUCUCGGCUGCAACCUCCGCCUCCCGGGUUCAAGCAAUUCUUGUCUCAGCCUCCCAAGUAGCUGGGAUUACAGGCACCCACCACCACACCCGGCUAAUUUUUGUAUUUUUCAGUAAAGACUGUUUCGCUGUGUUGGCCAGGCUGGUCUUGAACUUCUGACCUCAGGUGAUUGGCCUGUCUCCACUUCCCAAAGUGCUGAUUACAGGCCUGAGCCACUGCACCCAACAUUAUUUUCAAAAUGACAAGAGGUAGUAUUUAGUACCUGAGGCUCAGAUGUUAAACACAAACUCAGUAUUUACAAAAAUAAACAUUUAAAACAUUUACACUUCAACUUCCAAAAUGGCUUUUUACCAUAAACAUUCAGGAUUUUCAAACCUGUAACAGCUUAUCAAUGCAUCUCAUCUUAGAAGUAUGUUUUACAUUCUUCAUAAAAAUAAAAAUGAACCCAGGCUUCCUAAGAUUCAGGCCAGUGGGUCUCCACUUAAGGCCAAAUGGAGAAAUAAUUUUUUGCUGCCUAAACACACAAGUGAAUUGAAAAGCCACAGGCCAUUCAUUCAACAAAUAACUUUAUUAUUUUUAUUGAUAAUGUACUUGUAAUGUGCUAUUUUGAUACAUGUAUGCAAAGUAUAAUGGUCAAAUCAGGGUAUUUGAAUAUACAUAUAUUUCAAAAUAUAGUUAUAUAUUUCAAAAUAAGAUAUAGCAAGUUAGAAGUAUAUAUAAGUAUAUUAUUAUAUGUUAUUGUUAACUAUAAUUUACCUACUGUACUAUCAAAUACUAGAACUUAUUCCUUGUAUCUAAAUGUAUUCUUGUAACCAUUAACUAACUUUUCUGAAUUUCCUACUCUCCCCUUCCCUUCCCAGCCUUGUAACCACCUUUCUACUCUGCCUCCAUGAGACCCAUUUUUUAAUCUCCCACAUAUGAGUGAGAACAUUCAAUAUUUGUCUUUCUAGGCUUGGCUUAUUUCACUUACAUUAAUGACCUCCAGUUCCAUCCAUGUUGCUACAAAUGACAGAAUCCCAUUCUUUUUCAUAAUAUUGUCCAUACAUACCACAUUUUCUAUAUCCAUUUAUCUGUUGAUGGACACAGGUUGCAAAGGGAUUGCUGGAUUGUAUGAUAAUUCUAUGUGUAGUUUCUUGAGGAACCUUCAUGGUGUUCUUCAUAGUGGUUGUACUACUGUACAUUCCUACCAAUGGUGGAUGAGCGUUCCCCUUUCUCCACAUCCUCACAAGCAUUUGUUAUUUUUUCUUUUUUUUCAAAUGAACAUUUUAACUGGGGUGAGAUAUCUUAAUGUGGUAUUGGUUUACAUUUCCCUAAUUAUGGUUGAGCAUUUUUUCACAUAUCUAAUGGCCAUUCAUAUGUCUUCCUUUGAGAAAUGUCUAUACAGAUCUCUGGCCCUUUUUUUAAAUUUUUUUUUUUUUUGAAUUGGGGUCACCCAGUCUGGAGGUGAUCUGGGCUUCCACAUCCUGGGCUCAAGUGAUCAUUCCACCUCAGGAUGACCCAAAUAGCUAGGACCAAAGGCGAGUGCCACCAUGCUCAGCUAAUUUUUUUGUAUUUUUUGUAGCGACUGGGUUUCACCAUGUUGCCCAGGCUGGUCUUGAACUCCUGUGCUCAAGUGAUCCGCUCACCUUGGCCUCUCAAAGUGCAGGUACUUUAGGCGUGCCUGGCCUUUUUGUCCAUUUUAUUUUUUUGAGAUGGAGUCUUGCUGUGUCACCCAGGCUGGAGUGCAGUGGUGCGAUCUCGACUCAGUGCAACCUCCGCCUCCCAGGUUCAAGCAAUUCUCCUGCCUCAGCCUCCUGAGUAGCUGGGAUUACAGGUGUGCACCACCACACCCAGCUAAUUUUUUUGUAUUUUUAGUAGAGAGGGGGUGUCACCAUGUUGGCCAGGGUGAUCUUGAACUUCUGACCUUGUGAUCCACCCACCUUGGUCUCCCAAAGUGCUGGGAUUACAGGUGUGAGCCACUGCGCCCAGCCUGUCCAUUUUUUAAUCAGGUUAUGGGUUUUUUGCUAUUGAAUUGUUUGAGUUCCUUAUAUAUUCUGGUUAUGAAUCCCUUGUUAGAUGGUGUGUUAGGCCAUUCUUGUGUUGCUAUAAAGAAAAUCCUGAGUCUGGGUAAUUUAUAAAGAAAAAAGGUGUAAAUGGCUCAUAGUUCUGCAGACUGUACAGGAAGCAUGGCACCAGCAUUGCUUGGCUUCUGGGGAGGCCUCAAGGAACUUUCACUCAUAGCAGAAAGCAAAGCAGGAGCAGGCACAUCACAUGGCAAGAGAGCAAGAGAGAGAGGUGGAGGAGAUGCCACACACUGUUUUAAACAACCAGAUCUCUCAGGAACUCAUUGUUGUUAGAAAAGGAAUUAAAAGAAAUCAAAGAGUGUGUAAGCAGAAACUCAGUUGUACGUAAGAAAACCCAAUUCCCCCUGAGAAAGAGAAAGAGCUGGAGUCCUUUAAAAAUUCACUGCCUGUUUUUCUGGUGGCUAGUGAGUGUUAGCUCUCCUCCCUUCCCAGGCAUUGUGAAGACCCUGUUUCCCUAGCUGUGCAGCUGCAAGGUCACUAGACAGAUAAACUCAAGUCGCAAAACAUGUUUUUCCUUGAAAAGUAAGAAAUGAUGUAAUGCAUGUCUUGACUGAAUAACUGUCUUUGUUUCUUGCUUCUGUAAUAUGCUUCCCCCUGCACAGAUCUCCCCCUGCCCCACGAAAUGCUUAAAAGCUAACUUAACUCUUUGUUCAGGGCUCAGUCCUUUGGAUGUUAAUCUGACUGGGCCGGAGCACCUAAAUAAUAAAUAUUCUCCUGAACCCCA